GUCGUAUUUCCAAGGACUCCAAAGCGAGGCCGGGGACUGAAGGUGUGGGUGUCGAGCCCUCUGGCAGAGGGUUAACCUGGGUCAAAUGCACGGAUUCUCACCUCGUACAGUUACGCUCUCCCGCGGCACGUCCGCGAGGACUUGAAGUCCUGAGCGCUCAAGUUUGUCCGUAGGUCGAGAGAAGGCCAUGGAGGUGCCGCCACCGGCACCGCGGAGCUUUCUCUGUAGAGCAUUGUGCCUAUUUCCCCGAGUCUUUGCUGCCGAAGCUGUGACUGCCGAUUCGGAAGUCCUUGAGGAGCGUCAGAAGCGGCUUCCCUACGUCCCAGAGCCCUAUUACCCGGAAUCUGGAUGGGACCGCCUCCGGGAGCUGUUUGGCAAAGAUGAACAGCAGAGAAUUUCAAAGGACCUUGCUAAUAUCUGUAAGACGGCAGCUACAGCAGGCAUCAUUGGCUGGGUGUAUGGGGGAAUACCAGCUUUUAUUCAUGCUAAACAACAAUACAUUGAGCAGAGCCAGGCAGAAAUUUAUCAUAACCGGUUUGAUGCUGUGCAAUCUGCACAUCGUGCUGCCACACGAGGCUUCAUUCGUUAUGGCUGGCGCUGGGGUUGGAGAACUGCAGUGUUUGUGACUAUAUUCAACACAGUGAACACUAGUCUGAAUGUAUACCGAAAUAAAGAUGCCUUAAGCCAUUUUGUAAUUGCAGGAGCUGUCACGGGAAGUCUUUUUAGGAUAAACGUAGGCCUGCGUGGCCUGGUGGCUGGUGGCAUAAUUGGAGCCUUGCUGGGCACUCCUGUAGGAGGCCUGCUGAUGGCAUUUCAGAAGUACUCUGGUGAGACUGUUCAGGAAAGAAAACAGAAGGAUCGAAAGGCACUCCAUGAGCUAAAACUGGAAGAGUGGAAAGGCAGACUACAAGUUACUGAGCACCUCCCUGAGAAAAUUGAAAGUAGUUUACAGGAAGAUGAACCUGAGAAUGAUGCUAAGAAAAUUGAAGCACUGCUAAACCUUCCUAGAAACCCUUCAGUAAUAGAUAAACAAGACAAGGACUGAAAGUGCUCUGAACUUGAAACUCACUGGAGAGCUGAAGGGAGCUGCCAUGUCCGAUGAAUGCCAACAGACAGGCCACUCUUUGGUCAGCCUGCUGACAAAUUUAAGUGCUGGUACCUGUGGUGGCAGUGGCUUGCUCUUGUCUUUUUCUUUUCUUUUUAACUAAGAAUGGGGCUGUUGUACUCUCACUUUACUUAUCCUUAAAUUUAAAUACAUACUUAUGUUUGUAUUAAUCUAUCAAUAUAUGCAUACAUGAAUAUAUCCACCCACCUAGAUUUUAAGCAGUAAAUAAAACAUUUCGCAAAAGAUUAAAGUUGAAUUUUACAGUUCGUAUAUUCAUGUGGUCCUUUGAAAGGGUAUUCUAGAAAUCACUGGAAAGAGGAGAGGAAAGAACCAGGUAGGCAAAUGGUCUGUGAAACCCUUGGGUCCUGGAAGCAGUGUGAGUGUAAAUGUGUAGUGUUUGGUUUCAUCUAAAUAAACAAAGAUGAUUUCUUUGACACUUGAAAUAAAAUACAAAUUCAACAAAAAGUAGAUCAGCAUUAUUAAAGAAACGGUUCAACUUUGUUUCUUCCCUUAGUAUUGCUGACAAAGUAUCUGCUGUAGAAUACAGGAAUUACUUAGAAUAGAAACAUAGUCAUCACAACUGUUACUAAAUGGAAAAGAAAAGAAUUAUUGAGUUAAGUAUUCCUGUCAAUACGGGAAACACUGCUAGUACCUUAUGUUGGUGUUAGACCUCUCUGCCCUACACUGAGAAUAUAGUUUUACACAGGAGCAAGGUUUGUGAAGCAGCAUAGUGAGGUAGCUAAAGCCAUGGGCUGGCUCUAAAGGCUUUAAAUCCCAGCCAUGUGGCUUAGCUGCCAUGAGAUGUGCAUUUGAGAAAUGUUGUCUUCUUUUGCUGUUCAACUCCAGAUUUUCAGAUGAUAAUGUGAUUAUCCCAGCUUAAGUUGCGUCCACUUCUGGUCUAGUGAAUUGUGGAAGGCAGUUUUAGAGAAAGGAGUCAUGAGUAACAUGAACAGCAGUUGGCUAUGUCUUUCCAGUUCUCUGCUGAUGUCAGAAAGACCCAGAAAUACCAAGGAGAAAAAGCCAUCUUAGGGAUCUAAGGAGGCCCUAUGGAAAGUUACUACCUUAGACAUUUGAAGAUAGCUUACUGCUUAGUACAUACACUGUAAACAACGAUCUCAUUUUAAAUGAGAACUUUCUCAUAAAUAUUUUACAAAUGAGGUCAAACUAGCAUAAAGCCAUUUAAAGAGAUUAUCAGUCCAAUAUGAACCAGUUAAGUCUUUGGACUAUCCCUUUCCUCCUUGACUACUGCUUUGACGUACCUAAAUCAUUCGUCU